AAAAGUGUAAAAAUAUUUUCUAAUCACAUAUUUGGUAGGUGUUAAUUUCCAAAAGAUAUAAACUUCUAAAAUUCAACAACAACAAAAUGUUAAUAACUUGAUUUAGAAUGGUAAAUGUUUGAAAUGACCUUUCUCCAAAGAAGACAUAGAAAUGACUAGGUAUUUAAAAGGAUACUCGUCCGAGGGCAGGACUAUGGGAGGCUGCCCUGUACGGAAAAGAAGAAGAAAUGGCAGUAAAGAGGGCAACCAUCAUUCCACCCAGCCCAAAAGGAAUAAGAGAAACCCUAUCUUUCAGGAUUCUCAAGACACAGUUUUCAUGGAGUGAUAAUGAAAGGAGCAACAGCCGCCUUAAUAUCCCAGAGAGAGCAGGUGGACCAGAAGGCAACUUAAACCAGAUUGUUACUGAACCCAAUGCAAACUUUCCCCAGUUCUUGCAUGAGGGGUAUGUACCAUGCCAAGGUCUUUACUCCCAUAUCAACCAGACCUUGAAGGAGGCUCACUUCAACAGCCUGCAGCAGUGAGGGCAAGCUCCAACAUGAUGAAUUAGGACUUCCUUAUUCCAACCUAAACUGUGUUUAUAAAAGUAAUUGCAUACACACCAAAAAAAAAGUCUAUUGGUUUUUAAGACUAAAUUUUAAGUAACAAGUU